ACUACUGCGUCUCACACUUAGUCUCCAGGAGUAAUUGAAAAGCUCACGGUGACAAUUGUGUCUUCUUCCAGAUGUCAUCGCUAUAAGGAGUGGGGCUUUCAUCACCUCCUUGACGUAGGAUGUGUACAUGGCUCUCCAGGUCAGAGUUGCUCCAAGCAAGGUUGUUUUGCAGAAGUUUCUUCUAUGUGUCAUUCUUUUCUACACUGUGUACUAUGUGUCCCUGAGCAUGGGCUGCGUGAUGUUUGAGGUGCAUGAGUUGAAUGUCCUGGCUCCAUUUGAUUUCAAAACAAAUCCCUCAUGGCUCAACAUAAACUAUAAAGUUCUUUUAGUUUCAACAGAGGUCACCUACUUUGUUUGUGGAUUGUUUUUUGUUCCAGUUGUGGAAGAAUGGGUUUGGGAUUAUGCUAUUUCAGUCACUAUUCUUCAUGUUGCCAUCACUUCAACUGUUAUGUUGGAAUUCCCCUUGACAUCACAUUGGUGGGCUGCUUUAGGUAUAUCAAAAUUGCUUGUUUAGAUUCUCUAAUGCACAGAAAUAAUGUUAAAUAGAAUAACUGUGGAAAUAUAUUUUAUUUUCUCAUAGAUUUUACAA